AGGCGGCGGCGGCAGCGGCGGCGGUUGGUCAGGGGCGUGUUGGCCCCGCACAGAUUGAGCCGAGUUGUCGCCCCGCUGGGAGAAGUGACCCUCCUGCGCCUGUCCAUGCAGGGUCUAGAACGCCCACAUGUGCGGAACUGGGGAAUAGAGCUGGAGACCCUGCGCGAUGCCUUCCGCCCACAACCCUCAGUUUGGAGGACUGCCCGGGGAGAGGCUGGCAAAAGAAAGGGAAGGCUUGUAGAGUGCCUUGGAAGUCAGAGGAAAGUUUUGGAGGGCGUGCUCCUCUAUGCAGUCACCCGUGGUUCCUUUCCUAAUCUUUUCACACCGAGGGAUUGAAUGUUGUAAAUUUGAGUGCUUUGUGGCAUGGCAUGGUGGAAUAGCUGAUCCCCAGUGGUUGCAAAGAGAUGAUUUUAGGUCAGAGCCUGGGUUUUGCUUCGCUUGUGUGAAGAGCAAAAAACAAACAAACAAAAACAACAAGAACAACAGAACCGCUUUGUGAAUUGCUAUCUGAUCACCUGUCUUGGCACUUAAAUGAUUAGAAAUUGAAAUUCUCACCACCUCAGAUUCCCUUUGGGAACAAAUUGGAACUGUUUCAAAUGACAGAAGUGGAAACUCUAGUGAUCUGGUGUAGAUGCCGAUACCUGUUGUCUGACUCAUCUGUUUCAAAAUCUCAUUAGAAACCAACUGUCAUUGAACAGUCAAGUGUCUUGGCAAAUCUUCCUUUCUUCACGUAAGAUGUGUAUUGGCGGCAGCCGUGGGAGGUCCAGACACAGGUGGCCAUGGAACUCGCUGGUAAUAGAGGACACAUCUCUUAACUGGGUUGCUCUAAGAACUGAUGCCUAAACCAUCUCAGCAUGGCGUAUAAAGGAGAAGGUGGGCAUGGCCAGCCUCCCUCAGCUACACUGUCUCAGGUUAGCCCUGGAAGUCUUUACACACGUAGAACCCAUACCCAUAAUAUAUGUAUGGCAUCUGACUUUUUCUACCCAAAUAUGGGAGGUGUGGAAAGCCACAUUUACCAGCUCCCUCAGUGCCUGAUUGGAAGAGGGGAUAAGGUUAUAAUUGUCAUCCAUGCUUAUGGAAAUCGAAAAGGCAUCCGUUACCUCACUAAUGACCUCAAAGUCUAUUACUUGCCUCUGAAAGUCAUGUAUAACCAGUCUAUGGCCAUGACCCUCUUUCACAGUCUGCCAUUGCUCAAGUACAUAUUUGUUCAGGAGAGAGUCACAAUAAUCCAUUCACAUAGUUCAUUUUCUGCCAUGGCCCAUGAUGUUCUCUUCCAUGCCAAGACAAUGGGGCUUCAAACAGUCUUAACAGACCAUCCCCUUUCUGGAUUUGCUAAGGUCCAUUCAGUGCUUACAAACAAACUUCUAACUGUGUCUCUUUGUGACACAAGCCGUAUCAUUUGCGUUUCUUAUACUAGUAAGGAAAAUACCGUACUACGAGCGGCACUGAUUACUGAAAUAGUGUCUGUCAUUCCUAACGCUGUAGAUCCUAUUGACUUCACUCCAGACCCAUUUAGAAGGCAUGAUAGUAUAACUAUUGUUGUCAGCAGACUUGUUUACAGAAAGGGAACAAAUUUGGUUAGUGGUAUUAUACCCAAACUCUUGUCAGAAAUAUUAAGAUUUAAAUUUCAUAAUUGGAGGAGAGGGACCAAAGAGAAUCAUUUUGCAAGAAGUUCCGGAAAGAUACCAGUUGCAUGACAGGGUGCAUCUUUUGGGAGCUUUAGAACACAAGAAUGUUAGAAAUGUCUUAGUUCAAGGACAUAUUUUUCUUAAUACCUCCCUUACUGAAGCAUUCUGCAUGGCGAUCAUGGAAGCAGCCAGCUGUGGUUUACAGGUUGUAAGUACCAGGGUUGGUGGAAUUCCUGAGGUGCUUCCGGAAAAUCUUACUAUUUUAUGAGAAACUUCAGUAAAAUCUUUGUGUGAGGGAUUGGAAAAAGCUAUUUUCCAACUGAAGUCAGGGGCAUUGCUGGCUCCAGAAAAUAUCCGUAACAUAGUAAAGACUUUCCACACCUGAAGGAAUGUUGUGGAGAGAACUGAAAAAGCGUAUGACCAAGUAUCAGUGGAAUCUGUGUUGCCAAUGGACAAACAACUGGACAGACUUAUUUCUCACAGUGGACCAGUAACAGGCUACAUCUUUGCUUUGUUGGCUGUUUUCAACUUCCUCUUCCUCAUUUUCUUGAGAUGGAUGACUCCAGAUUCUUAUCAUUGAUACUGGAAUAGAUGCCACUGGGCCAAGGGGUGCCUGGACUCAUAAAUGUUCUCACAGUAAAAGAGGGGGUGAGAAUAUUAAGAUAUCUAAAACCAGGUAGAAGAGAGCCUACAUUGUAAGAUUUUAAACAUUUGUAAUAGUUGUAUUAAGACUAUGGAAAAUAACCUGCUUUUUGGGGGCUUGUGUUUUUUAUUAGUUUUUUAUAAGUUAAUUUAGUAAGUUAUGCUACUUCUAUAUCAUUCAAUGUUUUCUUUUGAGGAAAGAUAAAAACUUAGGCAAUUCCUGAGUGUAGAAACCUUGCACUUAUUUAAAAUUUAGAAGAGAACAUUUAAACCAUUCAGGUAUUAAAUUUUUCAGACUACUGAAAUCCCUGUAGCAGAGAUGUUUUAACAUUAUAUUUUGAGAGCUUUGGGUGCUGAAGGGCCAAACAUUUUCUGGGCAUUUUUUUGGCCAGUUUUUAAUGUUAUGCCAUUAGUUAGACACUCACUAGAUGUUUACAAGUUUUCUUCAGGGAAGUACAACAACUAUAUGAACUAUUUUAAGUCAUGUUUAUAUACAUUUAUUAGAAAUCUAAGUCAUGCCUUUAAACAUUUAUUAGGUUCACUCAGUAGGUGUUAACAUAAAAUUAACAGGUUCCUUGAGUAAGAUAGUCCAUCAGUUACCAGCACAUUUUGAGCACCUGCUAUAUGUGGAAUGUUGAACUAGAUGCUUCCUGCCGUUAAGGACCAGAAAUGCAUUAACUCUUUAUCAUUCAAAUGGCUUAUUUCAUCAUAGUCAUGGUUGAUAUAAGAUAUAUAGCCUACAUGCCAAAAAUGCUCAUGCCAGUUAAUGCCAGGAAAAAAAUCACCGACACACUACUAGUACUUCUUUGAUCCUGUUCUAUGCAUUCUCCUAGGUAGAGCCUUCAUCUUCCAUUGUGUUGAUGAAGAUAUUUUUUGCUUUUUAAAUACUAGGGACUGAUAUCACUGUUGAUAGUGCAGAGAAACCCUCCAUAAUUAAGUUUUCUGUAAAAGCCUUCGUGUUUUCUGAGCAGAAUGUACGAGGUGUGCCAUCCCAAAACCAGCUGCUACCCUGUCCUUUUAAUAUCAGAACACUGAGGCUCAGAGAAGUUAACUACUCCAAAGUCAUAUAGCCAGUAUUUUCUGGAGCUGUAAUUCAAAUCAGAUGUGUUCAAUACCUUCUACUACCCCAUUGCUGUCUUUAUGAUUUGUAACAGAUGGAGCCAUGACAUUUUGAAUUCUCCCCAUCAUACCGUAUAACGUGAGAAAGGAUUGAAAAUGUAAAAGAAAUUUCAUUUCAAUAUAGGUGACUAUGCAGCCUGCAAUUCAAGUAUGGUUUGGAGAAGAUCUGCCUCUAAGUCCUCGGAGUCCUCUGACUCCCAGACACGGACCAGGAUUGGCUAAUGUUUGUCAGUACGAUGAGUGGAUAGCUGUGAGGCAUGAAGCCACUUUGUUGCCCAUGCAAGAAGAUCUGUCAAUCUGGUUAUCUGGUUUAUUAGGUAUUAAAGUUAAGGCAGAAAAAUUAUUGGAAGAACUUGAUAAUGGAGUACUAUUAUGUCAACUGAUUGAUGUUCUUCAAAACAUGGUGAAAACAUGCAACUCUGAAGAAUCAGGGAAUUUUCCAAUGAGAAAAGUGCCCUGUAAGAAAGAUGCUGCAUCAGGUUCAUUCUUUGCUCGGGACAAUACCGCAAACUUCCUUCACUGGUGUAGGGACAUUGGGGUUGAUGAAACUUACCUCUUUGAAUCUGAAGGUUUAGUUUUGCACAAAGAUCCAAGACAGGUGUAUCUUUGUCUUCUUGAAAUUGGUCGAAUUGUGUCAAGAUACGGGGUUGAGCCACCAGUGUUAGUAAAACUUGAGAAAGAAAUUGAGUUAGAAGAGACUUUGCUUAAUACUUCUGGGCCUGAAGAUUCCAUCAGCAUUCCAAAAUCAUGCUGUCGGCAUGAAGAGCUACAUGAAGCUGUUAAACAUAUUGCUGAGGACCCUCCUUGUAGUUGUUCUCAUCGAUUUUCUAUUGAGUAUUUAUCUGAAGGACGGUACCGACUAGGGGAUAAAAUACUCUUUAUAAGAAUGCUUCAUGGAAAACAUGUCAUGGUUCGCGUUGGUGGAGGCUGGGAUACUCUUCAAGGAUUUUUGCUUAAAUAUGACCCCUGUCGAAUAUUACAGUUUGCCACAUUAGAACAAAAAAUUUUAGCAUUUCAAAAAGGAGUUUCUAAUGAAAGUGUACCUGAUUCGCCUGCCAGAACACCUCAGCCUCCUGAAAUGAAUCCUUUGUCAGCAGUUAACAUGUUUCAGAAACAAAAUUCAAAACCCAGCGUGCCAGUUAGUAUUCCAAAAAGCAAAGAAAAACAGGGACGUCCACCAGGUGCAUUGGUGCCAGCAUCUUCACUGAAAGGAGGUAAUCUGGGCUCUAUGUCAGUCCGUUCUAAAUUGCCAAAUUCUCCAGCAGCAUCUUCUCAUCCCAAGCUCAAGUCUUCAAAAGGCAUAACGAAGAAACCGCAGGCUCCUUCAAACAAUGCAUCAUCUUCACUUGCUUCAUUAAAUCCAGUAGGUAAAAACACUUCUUCACCAGCUUUACCAAGAACUGCACCUUGUAUAUCUGAGUCACCGAGAAAAUGUAUUUCAUCCCCCAAUACCCCCAAGGCCAAGGUUAUUCCAGCCCAGAAUUCAGCAGAUCUGCCCGAGUCCACACUUUUGCCAAAUAAGUGUUCAGGAAAAACUCAACCUAAGUAUUUGAAACAUAAUCAUAUUUCUUCCAGAGAUAAUGCAGUAUCUCACUUAGCUGCACAUUCAAAUUCAUCCUCAAAAUGUCCCAAGCUGCCUAAAGCAAAUAUACCUGUAAGACCUAAACCUUCUUUCCAGUCCUCUGCAAAAAUGACAAAAACCAGUUCCAAAACCAUAGCCACGGGUCUAGGAACACAGUCUCAACCAUCCGAUGGAGCCCCACAAGCAAAGCCAGUCCCAGCACAGAAACUUAAAUCGGCCUUGAAUUUAAAUCAGCCAGUUUCUGUGUCCUCAGUUUCUCCUGUAAAAGCCACACAGAAAUCAAAAGAUAAGAAUAUAGUUUCAGCUACCAAAAAGCAGCCUCAGAAUAAAAGUGCAUUUCAGAAGACAGGACCCAGCUCCUUGAAGUCUCCUGGCCGUACCCCACUGUCCAUCGUGAGCCUACCCCAGUCUUCUACCAAAACACAAACUGCACCGAAGUCAGCACAGACUGUCGCUAAGAGCCAGCAUUCAACUAAAGGGCCUCCCAGAAGUGGCAAAACCCCAGCUUCAAUCAGGAAACCACCCUCAUCUGUUAAGGAUGCAGAUAGUGGAGAUAAAAAACCUACUGCAAAGAAAAAGGAAGAUGAUGACCAUUAUUUUGUCAUGACUGGAAGUAAGAAACCUAGAAAAUAAAUACAUACUCAUUAUAAAAAAAGAGAAAAGGAAGAAUGAAUGUGUUAGCUUCACAUCUUAAAAGUUUCUCCUAUUUGUGUCUGUCUAAAUAGGUGCAGACACUAAGGAUAGUGAGGAUGGAGGCUGGGAUGAGGAAAGGGUUCAUCAGAAUUCACAUAUCUGAAUUCACUGGAAAGAGCCCUUCUGAAGCAAACAGUUGUAAAAUCACUGCAAGGUUUUUAUUAAUAAUAGACAUGUAUAUGAUUUUCAGUCUAUAGCAUCUUUGUUAACAUCUGCCUUUUGCAGGAAAUGUAAAAGUUAUUUAACACUACAAGAAUUUUAACAAUAGUUGCUCUAUUUUUGAAUAUGUAUUAAAUAUGGAGUUCAUAUACCUGCUAAUAUCAACGGUGGUGCUCUUACUAUUAGUUAAUUGCAUUUUGGUUAAAAAAAAAAAAGCAACAGUUUGGCACUUGUCCUACAAAAGGCACCUAAUUUAAUUUUCUGAUCAGGAUUGCCUGAUCCAACAGUGCUAAGUCAUGGCUGCUGCUGACUAGCUUGGCAUUAUUCUGUGUUAGGUAGAAUUCUUAUUAUUUAUUUUUUUAAGCUUUCCAAAUUGGAAGGAACUGAUUGUUUCAUGUGGCUUAUAUUUACAUUGGUAAUAUUUUGUCACCAAUAUUUUUGGUUAAAAAAAAUCCAACAAAUUAACUUACUGAAAUAUAAACAAAUUUUGUAAACAAUUUUUUAUAUUAUCUAUAAAAACGUAGACACCUUAUGUUUCACAUGUUGUGCAAUGUGACAGGGGAAGCUGAUUUAGUAGCUUUUAGCAUAUUAAAAAUAAUUUUUUAUAAUGUAAUUUCCUGUGAGUGCAGACCUGACAUUUUACAUUAAAAUAAUGUGAAACAUCAGAAUUAUGUUUUAACAACUUUAAAAUUAAGAUGAUGUUAAAAUAAUUUUAGAGUUAUGCUAUGUAAAAAUUCUAUCAUGAAAUUAUUUUUCUCUAGAUAGCACAAUACCAAUUUUAAUUAAUUUCUUCCAAUUAGGUUACUUUUCUUUAAUAAAGUUAUGCUGCCUUCAGUUUUCCAAUGGCAAGUAGACAGGAUAUGUUCAAGGUUUUCUGCACUGUAGGCACAGUCUCUCAAGCAUAUCCUGAUCAUGUAAUGACUGCAUAAACUCCAUCAACCUAAGGUGAUACUUGUAAAUAAUUUAUUUUUAAGGGAUGGUGACUUUAAAAAUUAUUAAUGAACUUUGAGAAGUUUUAAGAGUGCUUUUAAAACUUCACAGUAUUGCCAAUUAUCUUAGGUUAUUCAGUAUUCAGGUUUGUGUUUCUCUGUUUUAAACUAAAAUGUGUUUUCUGAAGAAAAAAAUAAUAGUUUACACAAAUGUACAAUCAUAGAAUAAGCAUUUUAAGCUGGCGACUAGUGUUCUAUAGAUUACAAAGCAAGAAAACUUUCUAUGAAGAUAAAUGACCUUUUGCCUGAAGAGUACAGAUAAAAUCAAAGAUGUGUGCAAGCUAGUUUUUGGAAGAAGUGAUGCUUCUCUUCUUUAAAGAGACAGUCACCAAAUACUUGGUUUAACUCGACUAUUGACUUGGGCAUUGAGAGAGAUGAUAUAUACAUCUUUGGAAAGUGAAGUCAAUGUUCAAGAGGUGAUAGAAGCUUUACUUUUUAGUGAUCAGAAAUAUUUAGUGCAUCUUUUCAGACAGGAAGAAUUUUAUCAUCAAGUAUUCCCUUAUAAAACCAAGUAACACUUCUUUAUCAGUAACUUUUAGAACUUAAAAGAAAGCAAAAAGUAAAUGGAAUUGUAGGCAAUUUAUGAAUCCUAGUAGAUUUUACAAUAUGUAAUUUAUGUUGUUUACAGUAUAUAAACACUAAGUUUUGUGUUAAAUGUGAUCAGGAAUAAAAGUAUCCCACAGGCAUCUGACACAAAUUCCAGAAUUAGCCAAAGAAUUGUUUAUUUGAGGCCAGGCAAUCCCAGCAUUUUGGGAAGCCAAGUUGGGCAGAUCACGAAGUCAGGAGUUCGAAAUCAGCCUGACCAACAUGGUGAAACCUCUUCUCUACUAAAAAUACAAAAUUAGCCGGGCAUGGUGGCACAUGCCUAUAAUCUCAGCUACUCAGGAGGCUGAGGCAGGAGGAUCGCUUGAACCCGGGAGGCAGAGGUUGCAGUGAGCCAAGAUUGCGCCACUGCACUCCAGCCUGGGCAACAGAGUGAGACUCUGUCUCAAAAAAAAAAAAAAAGAAAAAGAAAAGAAAAAGGUUUAUUUGAAUAAUUGGAAGUCAGUUUAUACAUUACUAUUUUUCAGCAGUAGGGAAUUUCUCCAAUUACAUUCAUGUUGAAUGAAUUUUUAUUUAUAUAUAGCUUACCCUUCCAAAAUAAAAGUGUUUUUUUAAUGUUGUUUUGUUUUGUUUUGUUUUUUUCCUUUUUUGAGACGGAGUUUCACUCUUGUUGCCCAGACUGGAGUGCAGUGGCACAAUCUCAGCUCAUUGCAACCUCUGCCUCCUGGGUUCAAGUGAUUCUGCUGCCUCAGCCUCCUGAGUGGUUGGGAUUACAGGCAUCCACCACCAGGCCCAGCUAAUUUUUUUGUAUUUUCAGUAGAGAUGGGGGUUUCACCAUGUCGGCCAGGCUGAUCUCAAACUCCUGACCUCAGGUGAUCCACCUGCCUCAGCCUCCCAAAGCGCUGGGAUUACAGGCAUGAGCCAUCACACCCAGCGAAAAGUUUUGUUUGAAUAAACAAUAUCCGAAAGACAAUUAGUUUCUUCAGAUGUAUUUUGAAAUUCUCCUAAAGAGCUAGUGUUUCUAUUCAUUUUCACAAUUUAAAAACAGCUCUUAACAUUGCUGAAGUUGGGAGAACUUUCCAUCUCUUCUUAAUAACAGUGCAAGAUUUUGUAAAUUCUUUUUUGUGUUUAAUGUUUAAUAAAACGAGUAUUAAGCUUAAAUUACUGAAGUACCUGGGAGAAGUAAUGAUGUGUACUUUCAAAAAAAUGGAAAAUGCUUUUAUUUUAUUUUCUAUAAUUUGUUAACAUGAUAUGUAAAAUUAAACUUCGGAGCACAAUGAAAUGCCGAUUAUUUUUACCUUGUUUGGGCUUAAAGUAGGUAUUUAAGGUUUAUGUGUUCAAAAUGCCUUGGUAAAUUGGAUGACCUCUAACUUUACUGUCCAUAUGGAGUUUGUCAUUCUUUAUGGAUAAGAGAACUUAAGGAAAAGUUACUGUUUUUCUUCAGUCUUUUUAUAUCUAUCUGAUUUAAAAUCUGUUACUUUAUUAAAAGGCUUCAACAACAGGUUGUUAGGAUGUAGUCUUACAUCCAGGUUCACAUAAUAACCCCAUUUGAAUCCAAAUUUGUGUAUAUUUUCUUAUGCCAGCAGUAUUUGUAUCCAAUUUUAACUUAGGUUUGUUUUCUUGAGUAUUAAAAUUUAAACAUAUAUA